AUUAUUUUAGCUUCCUGAGAUUCAGAGGCCAGGAACUGUGCAGAGAUCUGUGGGGAUUCUCACAACUUCCAUUUCUGGUGAACAGCUGAGGUCAGAGAGGAGGUGGGUACCACUUGAGAUGGGCCUGUGGUUCCCGGGUACUGUCUUUCCAGACACCUAGAAUUCCCAGGUUGGUAGUGAACUGAGAGUCAACCACCAUGAUGGGGCCAGAGACAGAGGAGGAAGCAGUGAGUGGAUAAGUGCCUGUGCUGGGCAGAAGGGAUAUAGGGGAAGGUGGCCAAAGGUAGGAUGGGGAAGUGGAUCCCAGGAAGCUUUUGUUUCUUCUGAGGCCAAUUUACCACCACCUCAUUGGGAAAUUGUUGGUAGGGAGGCACCCAUCCAAUUGCCUUGCAGAAUACAGCAAGGCAGGGAGCCCAAGAAUCAGAGCCAAGGGAAGAAACGACCAGUUGAGGUUAGUAAUGUGAAGUCUGGCAACCGUGCCCGUCAUUCCUCCCUGGUUCCUCUGUUCAUCAACGUUGGGGCUAGUCUGGCUGGGGCAUGGUGGGCCUGCCUUUCCAUCCCUUGGGCCCCUUGGAACAAGGGGGCAACUCUGCUGUGGGAGAUGUAGAAAAUGGGUCUCACUUUCUCUAUUUGGGGCAAUAGCUGCUACUUUUUUCCUCCAGAUGGGUACCAUGAGGGGCAGAGGAGAAUCUGGGAUCUGUGAUGUUUAGCCCUCUUUACUGAGUCAUGGCUGCCUCACGUUCUAGAAGUAAGGCAGGCAAAUCAUUCCAGGUACUGAUUGUCCUGGAACCUUUGGCUCUUCCUUGACCUCAUGUCACGUGCGUCCAUGUGAAGAGAGUCCACGAAACGGGCUUUAUAUGAGCAACAAGGCUGGGUGCAGGCAAGCUGAGUCCAAAAAAGGGGUCAGCAAAGGGUGGUGGCAUUAUCAUUAGUUCUUAUAUGUUUGGGAUAGGCUUACAAAGUACAUUCUCAAGGGUGGAGAAAUAUUACAAAGUACCUUCUUAAGGGCAGGGGAGAAUAUUACAAAGUACCUUCUUAAGGGCGGCGGCGGGGAGACUAUAUUGUAUCAGGGUGGGGCAGGAACAAAUCACAAUGGUGGAAUGUCAUCAGUUAAGGCUAUUUUCAUUUCUUUUGUGGAUCUUCAGUUGCUUCAGGCCAUCUGGAUGUAUACAUGCAGGUCACAGGGAAUAUGAUGGCUUAGCUUGGGUUCAGAGGCCUGACACCUCAGGCUGCCAAAUGUGGAAGAUUUAAAUACUUGAACCAAUACCCUCCUCCCAAAAACUGAAAUUGGCUUCUGUUUCUGAGUUGGUCCAGGCGCAAUGUUCAGCGUAUUUGAGGAAAUCACAAGAAUUGUAGUUAAGGAGAUGGAUGCUGGAGGGGAUAUGAUUGCCGUUAGAAGCCUUGUUGAUGCUGAUAGAUUCCGCUGCUUCCAUCUGGUGGGGGAGAAGAGAACUUUCUUUGGAUGCCGGCACUACACAACAGGCCUCACCCUGAUGGACAUUCUGGACACAGAUGGGGACAAGUGGUUAGAUGAACUGGAUUCUGGGCUCCAAGGUCAAAAGGCUGAGUUUCAAAUUCUGGAUAAUGUAGACUCAACGGGAGAGUUGAUAGUGAGAUUACCCAAAGAAAUAACAAUUUCAGGCAGUUUCCAGGGCUUCCACCAUCAGAAAAUCAAGAUAUCGGAGAACCGGAUAUCCCAGCAGUAUCUGGCUACCCUUGAAAACAGGAAGCUGAAGAGGGAACUACCCUUUUCAUUCCGAUCAAUUAAUACGAGAGAAAACCUGUAUCUGGUGACAGAAACUCUGGAGACGGUAAAGGAGGAAACCCUGAAAAGCGACCGGCAAUAUAAAUUUUGGAGCCAGAUCUCUCAGGGCCAUCUCAGCUAUAAACACAAGGGCCAAAGGGAAGUGACCAUCCCCCCAAAUCGGGUCCUGAGCUAUCGAGUAAAGCAGCUUGUCUUCCCCAACAAGGAGACGAUGAAUAUUCAUUUCAGGGGCAAAACAAAAUCCUUUCCAGAAGAGAAGGAUGGUGCUUCAUCCUGUUUAGGAAAGUCUUUGGGUUCGGAGGAUUCCAGAAACAUGAAGGAGAAGUUGGAGGACAUGGAGAGUGUCCUCAAGGACCUGACAGAGGAGAAGAGAAAAGAUGUGCUAAACUCCCUCGCUAAGUGCCUCGGCAAGGAGGAUAUUCGGCAGGAUCUAGAGCAAAGAGUAUCUGAGGUCCUGAUUUCCGGGGAGCUACACAUGGAGGACCCAGACAAGCCUCUCCUAAGCAGCCUUUUUAAUGCUGCUGGGGUCUUGGUAGAAGCGCGUGCAAAAGCCAUUCUGGACUUCCUGGAUGCCCUGCUAGAGCUGUCUGAAGAGCAGCAGUUUGUGGCUGAGGCCCUGGAGAAGGGGACCCUUCCUCUGUUGAAGGACCAGGUGAAAUCUGUCAUGGAGCAGAACUGGGAUGAGCUGGCCAGCAGUCCUCCUGACAUGGACUAUGACCCUGAGGCACGAAUUCUCUGUGCGCUGUAUGUUGUUGUCUCUAUCCUGCUGGAGCUGGCUGAGGGGCCUACCUCUGUCUCUUCCUAACUACAAAAGCCCUUUCUCCCCACAAGCCUCUGGGUUUUCCCUUUACCAGUCUGUCCUCACUGCCAUCGCCACUACCAUCCUGUCACCAGUGGGACCUCUUUAAAACAAGCAGCCAACCAUUCUUUGAUGUAUCCCAUUCGCUCCAUGUUAACAUCCAAAACCAGCCUGGAUUUCAUACAUGGACUUCUGAUUAAAAGUGGCAGGUUGUGCAUGUUAA